AUUAUUGAUCUGAAGGGUAAAUGUGGAGGGAGCCACAGAGAGGGGUCCAGGCUUUUCUGAGAAGAGAGGCAGCCUCUUCCAGGAAGAAAGUGGUGUCUACUGGCUGCCCGGCCUGGAGAACCUUCUUUGAAUGAAAACGGACAAAAUGCAAAGCAGUGUGUUGGCACAGUGAUUUGGAAAGGGGAAACAGAAGAGAAGGGUCUCACCUUCCGCGCAAGGCUGAGCUGUUGGCACCCUGCUGCGGCCGUCGGUGCUGCUGCUCCUGCAGCUGCCUUUUCUGCCAUCAGAGAUGGAGUCUCAGUAUGUUUACCAGACUUGUUUCUAACUUCUGACAUCAAGCGAUUCUUCCCCCUCAGCCUUCCAAAGUGCUGGGAUUACAGCUUUGUUACCUAACAGCUUGGCUCUUUUGGGAAAUAUAGACAAGCUGGAACCCAGGAGCAGUUGGGAGUUUUAAAGAAUGCCAGCCUUUUUAAAGCUUUGAUGUCCAGUGCUAUAGAAUCAAGUUACUGUGGAGGUCAAAACAAUUUGAGAUACAUAAGCUGGCCUUAGAAAAUAAAUUGCCUCUAACUUACAGUGAGGAGCUCAACAUAACAGGGAAAAGGAGCACAGGAUGCAGCUACUUGGAGGGUGUUGAUUGAAAACUUCGAUCUCCCCACCCCAUUCACGGUUGAUUUGACGGAUUUCUCACCUCGUUCACAGAGAAAAUUUCAAUUAAGAUCCUGAUGUGUGUCAAUUGGUAGAUGGAGCUGCUUCCGUCAUCUUCAAGGAGGAGAUAAGAGGCUCAGGCCCCUUUAGAUGGAAUAUAAUACAGCAGAAGCCUUUUCAUCAAAAGGAUUAAUGCCUGCAUCAUCAUUUCUGCAAUAAAACAAGAAGCUAAGUGGUGGAGGCCACAGACACCUCAAACCUGGAUUCCACAAUUCUACGUUAAGUGUUGGAGUUUUUAUUACUCUGCUGUAGGAAAGCCUUUGCCAAUGCUUACAAGGAACUGUUUAUCCCUGCUUCUCUGGGUUCUGUUUGAUGGAGGUCUCCUAACACCACUACAACCACAGCCACAGCAGACUUUAGCCACAGAGCCAAGAGAAAAUGUUAUCCAUCUGCCAGGACAACGGUCACAUUUCCAACGUGUUAAACGUGGCUGGGUAUGGAAUCAAUUUUUUGUGCUGGAAGAAUACGUGGGCUCCGAGCCUCAGUAUGUGGGAAAGCUCCAUUCCGACUUAGACAAGGGAGAGGGCACUGUGAAAUACACCCUCUCAGGAGAUGGCGCUGGCACCGUUUUUACCAUUGAUGAAACCACAGGGGACAUUCAUGCAAUAAGGAGCCUAGAUAGAGAAGAGAAACCUUUCUACACUCUUCGUGCUCAGGCUGUGGACAUAGAAACCAGAAAGCCCCUGGAGCCUGAAUCAGAAUUCAUCAUCAAAGUGCAGGAUAUUAAUGAUAAUGAGCCAAAGUUUUUGGAUGGACCUUAUGUUGCUACUGUUCCAGAAAUGUCUCCUGUGGGUGCAUAUGUACUCCAGGUCAAGGCCACAGAUGCAGAUGACCCGACCUAUGGAAACAGUGCCAGAGUCGUUUACAGCAUUCUUCAGGGACAACCUUAUUUCUCUAUUGAUCCCAAGACAGGUGUUAUUAGAACAGCUUUGCCAAACAUGGACAGAGAAGUCAAAGAACAAUAUCAAGUACUCAUCCAAGCCAAGGAUAUGGGAGGACAGCUUGGAGGAUUAGCCGGAACAACAAUAGUCAACAUCACUCUCACCGAUGUCAAUGACAAUCCACCUCGAUUCCCCAAAAGCAUCUUCCACUUGAAAGUUCCUGAGUCUUCCCCUAUUGGUUCAGCUAUUGGAAGAAUAAGAGCUGUGGAUCCUGAUUUUGGACAAAAUGCAGAAAUUGAAUACAAUAUUGUUCCAGGAGAUGGGGGAAAUUUGUUUGACAUCGUCACAGAUGAGGAUACACAAGAGGGAGUCAUCAAAUUGAAAAAGCCUUUAGAUUUUGAAACAAAGAAGGCAUACACUUUCAAAGUUGAGGCUUCCAACCUUCACCUUGACCACCGGUUUCACUCGGCGGGCCCUUUCAAAGACACAGCUACGGUGAAGAUCAGCGUGCUGGACGUAGAUGAGCCACCGGUUUUCAGCAAGCCGCUCUACACCAUGGAGGUUUAUGAAGACACUCCGGUAGGGACCAUCAUUGGCGCUGUCACUGCUCAAGACCUGGAUGUAGGCAGCAGUGCUGUUAGGUACUUCAUAGAUUGGAAGAGUGAUGGGGACAGCUACUUUACAAUAGAUGGAAAUGAAGGAACCAUCGCCACUAAUGAAUUACUAGACAGAGAAAGCACUGCGCAGUAUAAUUUCUCCAUAAUUGCGAGUAAAGUUAGUAACCCUUUAUUGACCAGCAAAGUCAAUAUACUGAUUAAUGUCUUAGAUGUAAAUGAAUUUCCUCCAGAAAUAUCUGUGCCAUAUGAGACAGCCGUGUGUGAAAAUGCCAAGCCAGGACAGAUAAUUCAGAUAGUCAGUGCUGCAGACCGAGAUCUUUCACCUGCUGGGCAACAAUUCUCCUUUAGAUUAUCACCUGAGGCUGCUAUCAAACCAAAUUUUACAGUUCGUGACUUCAGAAACAACACAGCGGGGAUUGAAACCCGAAGAAAUGGAUACAGCCGCAGGCAGCAAGAGUUGUAUUUCCUCCCUGUUGUAAUAGAAGACAGCAGCUACCCUGUCCAGAGCAGCACAAACACAAUGACUAUUCGAGUCUGUAGAUGUGACUCUGAUGGCACCAUCCUGUCUUGUAAUGUGGAAGCAAUUUUUCUACCUGUAGGACUUAGCACUGGGGCGUUGAUUGCAAUUCUACUAUGCAUUGUUAUACUCUUAGCCAUAGUUGUACUGUAUGUAGCACUGCGAAGGCAGAAGAAAAAAGACACCCUGAUGACCUCUAAAGAAGACAUCAGAGACAACGUCAUCCAUUACGAUGAUGAAGGAGGUGGGGAGGAAGAUACCCAGGCUUUCGACAUCGGGGCUCUGAGAAACCCAAAAGUGAUUGAGGAGAACAAAAUUCGCAGGGAUAUAAAACCAGACUCUCUCUGUUUACCUCGUCAGAGACCACCCAUGGAAGAUAACACAGACAUAAGGGAUUUCAUUCAUCAAAGGCUACAGGAAAAUGAUGUGGAUCCAACUGCCCCACCAUACGAUUCACUGGCCACAUAUGCCUACGAAGGGAGUGGGUCCGUGGCAGAGUCCCUCAGCUCUAUAGACUCUCUCACCACAGAAGCCGACCAGGACUAUGACUAUCUGACAGACUGGGGACCCCGCUUUAAAGUCUUGGCAGACAUGUUUGGCGAAGAAGAGAGUUAUAACCCUGAUAAAGUCACUUAAGGGAGUCGUGGAGGCUAAAAUACAACCGAGAGGGGAGAUUUUUAAAAAAGAAAAAGAAACACAAAUAUUAAUAGAAAUCUCUCUCACACACACACACACACACAAACACACACACACACACACACACUCUGGGACAAGAUUCCUUUGAUUACCUGGUUUCUAGUAAGUUACUAAAUUAAUCAUAUUGUCAGUUUUGGUUUAUUCUGCCAACAAGAGAUACAUCCUAUAAUGUGUACUUGCUUUGUUUUGUUGUUUUGUUUUUUCACAAUCACACUGAGACAAGCUCAGGCCUAUUCAAUACAAUUUACUGACAUGACAACCUAGAACGAAGAUAGCUAUGUGGCAUCACGGUGGAAGAGUGUUAGAUUUUUCUUAAUUCCACUAAAGUGCCUAUUGAAACUCUUAUCAUUUAAAGUGGUGUACAGUACACUCUGCUGUGAUGGUAUUGCGGGAUUCAGAGAUAAAGACAUAAAACAAAGACACCGUCUUUAUGUCAAGAAGCAAUAGCGACACUCUGACUCUCCUCAUUCCUUUUGAGAACAAAAGAAGAACACUUUCUGAUCUCCACCUUCUUCUAAUUCAAAAGGUUUUCUUUUUCUUUUUUAAACUGUAUGCUAAAACGUAUUUGUUUAUCCUAUCCUUUCAGAAAAUUGAAAUAAAUAUGAAAAUAUCAAGUUCAAUAUGUAAGUCCCAAAUUCUAGAAACAAUGUUUGAUCUUAACAUUAGUUCACAUUAAAGCUGUUCAUUAAAAUGUUACUUUCUUUUCCAAAAAAAAAAGAAAGAAAAAAAAGAAAAAAUAUUCCUCUUUAUAAAGAGAGGCCUCAGGGCUCAAAUUACACAUUAAAAUAAAUAUUGGUUUUGCUUAAUAUUGUACUGGUGUGUGGAAAAUUGGUUUUAACAGUCACCAGAUUCAGCUUUUAGUCAUAGAUGUAAUUUCAAGUUGUGUUUCUAUGAAAAUUCUUAGAAGAAAAAAGUGCCAUUCAUUUAAGCAUGGAAAGAGAAAUUCAUUAUACAGUUUCUCAGAGUUUCUUACAAUCUAGUGAUUCUUUGAUGAGCAGCAAAAA